GGGGCUGGCCAGGGUGUGACCACCGUGCUGGGCAGCAGGCUCCAGUCCCUAACCCCCAGCCACUACUGGCAUGAGGGGUCCCUCAGGGCCCCCAGGCCUCCUCUACGUCCCACACCUCCUCCUCUGCCUGCUCUGCCUCCUCCCACCGCCGCUCCAAUACGCAGCCGGGCAGAGCCAGAUGCCCAAAGACCAGCCCCUGUGGGCACUUCUGGAGCAGUACUGCCACACCAUCAUGACCCUCACCAACCUCUCAGGCUGGUCUUGAAUUCCUGUGCUCAAGCAAUCUGCCUACCUUGGCUUCCCCAAGUGCUGAGAUUAUGGGUGUGAGCCACUGCACCUGGCCAAGAAUCCGAAUGGAUUCAAAGAUACCUUGAAAUAAUUCCUCAAUGCAACACACACACAUAUGCCAGGGUUGGUCAAAUGGGAAGAGAGCCUUGGCCUGAAGACAGGGACCUGGGCUUUCCUCAGCUCUUCUGCCAAGGUCCCUACUCCUACUGCAACACGACCUUGGACCAGAUCGGAACGUGCUGGCCCCGCAGCGCUGCCGGAGCCCUCGUGGAGAGGCCGUGCCCCGAGUACUUCAACGGCGUCAAGUACAACACGACCCGGAAUGCCUAUCGAGAAUGCUUGGAGAAUGGGACGUGGGCCUCAAAGAUCAACUACUCACAGUGUGAGCCCAUUUUGGAUGACAAGCAGAGGAAGUAUGACCUGCACUACCGCAUCGCCCUUGUCGUCAACUACCUGGGCCACUGCGUAUCUGUGGCAGCCCUGGUGGCCGCCUUCCUGCUUUUCCUGGCCCUGCGGAGCAUUCGCUGUCUGCGGAAUGUGAUUCACUGGAACCUCAUCACCACCUUUAUCCUGCGAAAUGUCAUGUGGUUCCUGCUGCAGCUCGUUGACCAUGAAGUGCACGAGAGCAAUGAGGUCUGGUGCCGCUGCAUCACCACCAUCUUCAACUACUUCGUGGUGACCAACUUCUUCUGGAUGUUUGUGGAAGGCUGCUACCUGCACACGGCCAUUGUCAUGACCUACUCCACUGAGCGCCUGCGCAAGUGCCUCUUCCUCUUCAUCGGAUGGUGCAUCCCCUUCCCCAUCAUCGUCGCCUGGGCCAUCGGCAAGCUCUACUAUGAGAAUGAACAGUGCUGGUUUGGCAAGGAGCCUGGCGACCUGGUGGACUACAUCUACCAAGGCCCCAUCAUUCUCGUGCUCCUGAUCAAUUUCGUAUUUCUGUUCAACAUCGUCAGGAUCCUAAUGACAAAGUUACGCGCGUCCACCACAUCCGAGACAAUCCAGUACAGGAAGGCAGUGAAGGCCACCCUGGUGCUCCUGCCCCUCCUGGGCAUCACCUACAUGCUCUUCUUCGUCAAUCCCGGGGAGGACGACCUGUCACAGAUCAUGUUCAUCUAUUUCAACUCCUUCCUGCAGUCGUUCCAGGGUUUCUUCGUGUCUGUCUUCUACUGCUUCUUCAAUGGAGAGGUGCGCUCAGCCGUGAGGAAGAGGUGGCACCGCUGGCAGGACCAUCACUCCCUUCGAGUCCCCAUGGCCCGGGCCAUGUCCAUCCCUACAUCACCCACACGGAUCAGCUUCCACAGCAUCAAGCAGACGGCCGCUGUGUGACCCCUCGGUCGCCCACCUGCACAGCUCCCCUGUCCUCCUCCACCUUCUUCCUCUGGGUUCUCUGUGCUGGGCAGGCUCUCGUGGGGCAGGAGAUGGGAGGGGAGAGACCAGCUCUCCAGCCUGGCAGGAAAGAGGGGGUGCGGCAGCCAAGGGGGACUGCAAGGGACAGGGAUGAGUGGGGGCCACCAGGCUCAGCGCAAGAGGAAGCAGAGGGAAUUCACAGGACCCCCUGAGAAGAGCCAGUCAGAUGUCUGCAGGCAUUUGCCCAUCCCAGCCUCUCUGGCCAGGGCCUUACUGGGCCCAGAGCAGAGAAGGACCUGUCCAACACACACAGCUAUUUAUAGUAGCAGACACAGGGCUCCCCUGCCCUACUCAUGGAGCCAGCAGCCAGGCAAUGGUGUGGCCCUGCACUGGCCCUUGGCCUCCACACUCAGUGGUGCCCCUGCAGUUGGGUGGGGUACGCCAGCAAAGGAUCAGUUUGGCUGCCUUAUCCCAGGGGCUGUCACCUAGAGAGGCUCACUUGUACCCCACCCUUGUUCCUGUGUCCCCUCCCCAGCCAUCCUCCCGCCUUGGGGGCUCCAUGAAGGAUGCAGGCUUCCAGGCCUGGCUUCCUCUCUUGGGAGACCCCUUCUCUGCCUAGUCCACAGAUUAGGCAAUCAAGGAAGACGCCAUCAGGGAAGCCACAUCCUUAGUCAACCAGUUGCAUCGUGCGGGGCAAAAUGAGGAGCAGAGGCAUGGAGGAGGGAGGCGUGGGAUGGGAAUAGCAGAAACCAACCAUGUCUUCAGUGAUUGAAACUCAUACCCCAUUGCCCUUUGCCCUCCAGUCUCCCCUUCAGAAACAUCUCUGCUCUCUGUGAAAUAAACCAUGCCUCUUGGAAGUGGCCUCCCCUCAGGUCAAGUCACCCAGGCACCCGAAGAGUGGUGUGGGCCAAGGAUCGUGGCUGGGUCUGAGGGGGCCACAUCCAUCUUCCUUAGUGGGCUCGGGCCCUGGCCUCGGGCCAGUUCUCUCUCUCUCUGACCUCUGGUAGGUUUGGAGUCUUUAUGGUCAAAGCACCUGCAGGCGGGUCUGUCCCUUAUCACUCCAACCAGGCUAAUACCUGGCCCCAGCCCCCAACCAAGGGCAGCUUGAUUCAGCCUGGAGGAGGUGUGCAGCUCAUCCAGCAAGCCAGGGCCUGUCCCAAAGGCCAAGGCUCUGGAAUCUGGUGGGCAGGGUAGACAUGGCCCCUCAGUUGACCACCAGGGCAGCUUCCAGGCUUGGCUUCCGUCCCUGUGUCCCUGCAGCGGAGCCGCAGGAGUCAGGGAGAGAGAAGCAUCAGGCCAUUUCUUCCAAAAGAAACCAAUGCUCUAGGUACCCCCUACAAAAAUAAGUUUUGAAAAAUCAUGUAUCCCGUCUUGCACAUUUUUAAGUUGACAUGUAGUAUUUUUUACUUAAGUUUUAAAUCCUUCAAAGGUGUGAUUUCUGCCAUUUUGUAAAUAUUUACAUUUUUAAAUAAAACUGCUGCAACAAUUUAAAAUAC